AGCGCGGAGCACCUGCGCCCGCGGCUGACACCUUCGCUCGCAGUUUGUUCGCAGUUUACUCGCACACCAGUUUCCCCCACCGCGCUUUGGAUUAGUGUGAUCUCAGCUCAAGGCAAAGGUGGGAUAUCAUGGCAUCUAUCUGGGUUGGACACCGAGGAACAGUAAGAGAUUAUCCAGACUUUAGCCCAUCAGUGGAUGCUGAAGCUAUUCAGAAAGCAAUCAGAGGAAUUGGAACUGAUGAGAAAAUGCUCAUCAGCAUUCUGACUGAGAGGUCAAAUGCACAGCGGCAGCUGAUUGUUAAGGAAUAUCAAGCAGCAUAUGGAAAGGAGCUGAAAGAUGACUUGAAGGGUGAUCUCUCUGGCCACUUUGAGCAUCUCAUGGUGGCCCUAGUGACUCCACCAGCAGUCUUUGAUGCAAAGCAGCUAAAGAAAUCCAUGAAGGGCGCGGGAACAAACGAAGAUGCCUUGAUUGAAAUCUUAACUACCAGGACAAGCAGGCAAAUGAAGGAUAUCUCUCAAGCCUAUUAUACAGUAUACAAGAAGAGUCUUGGAGAUGACAUUAGUUCCGAAACAUCUGGUGACUUCCGGAAAGCUCUGUUGACUUUGGCAGAUGGCAGAAGAGAUGAAAGUCUGAAAGUGGAUGAGCAUCUGGCCAAACAAGAUGCCCAGAUUCUCUAUAAAGCUGGUGAGAACAGAUGGGGCACGGAUGAAGACAAAUUCACUGAGAUCCUGUGUUUAAGGAGCUUUCCUCAAUUAAAACUAACAUUUGAUGAAUACAGAAAUAUCAGCCAAAAGGACAUUGUGGACAGCAUAAAAGGAGAAUUAUCUGGGCAUUUUGAAGACUUACUGUUGGCCAUAGUUAAUUGUGUGAGGAACACGCCGGCCUUUUUAGCCGAAAGACUGCAUCGAGCCUUGAAGGGUAUUGGAACUGAUGAGUUUACUCUGAACCGAAUAAUGGUGUCCAGAUCAGAAAUUGACCUUUUGGACAUUCGAACAGAGUUCAAGAAGCAUUAUGGCUAUUCCCUAUAUUCAGCAAUUAAAUCGGAUACUUCUGGAGACUAUGAAAUCACACUCUUAAAAAUCUGUGGUGGAGAUGACUGAACCAAGAAGAUAAUCUCCAAAGGUCCACGAUGGGCUUUCCCAACAGCUCCACCUUACUUCUUCUCAUACUAUUUAAGAGAACAAGCAAAUAUAAACAGCAACUUGUGUUCCUAACAGGAAUUUUCAUUGUUCUAUAACAACAACAACAAAAGCGAUUAUUAUUUUAGAGCAUCUCAUUUAUAAUGUAGCAGCUCAUAAAUGAAAUUGAAAAUGGUAUUAAAGAUCUGCAACUACUAUCCAACUUAUAUUUCUGCUUUCAAAGUUAAGAAUCUUUAUAGUUCUACUCCAUUAAAUAUAAAGCAAGAUAAUAAAAAUUGUUGCUUUUGUUAAAA